AGUCUCCUUCCACAAAACCAUGGCGUCGCUCAAAUGUAGCACCGUCGUCUGCGUGAUCUGCUUGGAGAAGCCCAAAUACCGCUGUCCAGCCUGCCGCGUGCCCUACUGCUCGGUAGUCUGCUUCCGGAAGCACAAAGAACAGUGCAACCCUGAAACUCGUCCUGUUGAGAAAAAAAUAAGAUCAGCUCUUCCUACCAAAACCGUAAAGCCUGUGGAAAACAAAGAUGAUGAUGACUCUAUAGCUGAUUUUCUCAAUAGUGAUGAGGAAGAAGACAGAGUUUCUUUGCAGAAUUUAAAGAAUUUAGAUGGACUCUCGUCCUGUCACCCAGGCUGGAGUGCAGCGGCGCAAUCUCGGCUCACUGCAACCUCUCCCUCCCAGAUUCAAGCAAUUCUCAUGCCUCAGCCUCCCGAGCAGCUGGGACUACAGGCGCCUGCCACUACGCCCAACCAAUUUUUGUAUUUUUAGUAGAGAUGGGGUUUCGCCAUGUUGGCCAGGCUGGUCUUGAACUCCUGACCUCAGGUGAUACACCCGCCUCGACUUCCCAAAGUACUGGGAUUAUAGGCGUGAGCCACCGCUCCAGGCCCUAAGCUAAACUUUCAUCACCUCCUGCUCCUGACUCAUCUAAAGCCUUGGUUCUCACAGUGUGGUUCAUGGAGCAUCAGAAUCAGCUGGGAGCUUGCUAGAAACGCAGCAUUGCAUUUGGAAAUGGGACUAGAAGAUUUAGAGAUGCUGAAAUAAUUAGAAGCAGUUUUUAAAAAGAUAAAGGGCUCUGGAAGAUUCCCAGUUAUAACAAAAUAAAUAAUCCAAACCUGCAGCUGAUUGGGACAUGCAGCCCUCUGGUUUACCCAGUAGGGUUAGGGAUGGAUCUUGUCCCAGCCUCAGUCUCAUUCCCGCUGUGAACUUGUAGGCUUUGCUCCUGCUGUUCUCAGGAACAAAGCUGUCAUGGCCAUCACACACAACGUACCUGAGGCAGCGCUCGGAUGGACGUGACACCAGCCUGGUCUUGUGCUGUCUGGACAGUGUAGCUACUGGGGCUGCCCCUGGGGAGCUGGAGGCAAGCCCAGACCACUAAUUUCCUCUGAAAGCUGCCUACACCCAUAGCCGUAUUGGCCAGGACCAGUCCCAGGGGCCAGAGGCGGAUUAUUGCCUCCAGGAGCCUGGUCUGCAGCGGCGAGGUGCUCAGGGAACAGGGAGCUUGAGAGAAGUGUUUUUCUUCCACACCAUCCAGCUCUUUAGCAGCAAGGCAGGCCAUUCUGAUCUUAAAAAGCAAAUAUCCCUUUAUAGCUUUAGAUUUAUCUAGCCCUCUUAGCAGAAAAUGGAAAUCAAAACUAUCUUUAACAAAUCAUCUUAACAAGGUGAACUGAAGGCACCUGGUUGCAAACAGCUGGCUGCCCUGAACCAAACUGGUUCCAUAUGCCACAAGUCUAUACACCCCAGGCAACUGUGCUUAGGCCUUACAUAUGCUACUUGAAAACAAGAUAAGAGUCCAUCAAGAUAUAACUGAUAUGCCAUAAAACCCAGUCUUCUAAAGUGUACAUCCCAGAGUUUGGUAUAUUCCCAGAGUUGCUUAUACCACUCUUCACCUACAUAACCACCCUGCAGGGUAGGUGUUACUGUGCCCACUGCAUACAUGAGGAAUAUGAGGCUCAGAGAGGCUAAACAACCUGCCCAAGGCCACCUGCAUUGCAGUGGCAGAGCCAGCAUUCCCACUCGGGUCCAUCUGGUCCCCAAAAUUGAUCCACUGCCCACCCCGACUUCUUGGGUCUUACUUACUCUCCACUUCUGCCAUGCACGCUUGAUGACUGUGGCAGCUGCAUGCAGCCUCUGGAUGUGUUUCCGAGUUAACCAGGAACGAAUGGCUAAGAGGUUUGCCCAGAAACAGGAAAGAGAUAAUAAAGGGGCCAUUAGAGCUGUCAGUGACCUCGCUGCAGCAGCACCACAGUUGCUGUCAAAGUUUCAAAUACGUUUUUUUUUUUUCAAUAAAUUGCUACAAAUAAGGUUCUAAAAUCAA